AAAAGGAAAUGGUACAGAGCAGCCUGUUGAAAUUAGACAGCAGGGUCACCCUGGUCCUCUGUGCCACAGGAAGGAGGGGUACUGAAGUGUCAGUUGUUGGUGGGGGAGCAGUGCUGCAGUGGGAAUUCCAGAGCUGAGAAGGCUGCCAUCAACCAAGUGAGACAUGACCAGCCCCCGAGUUGCUGCAGCAAACGAGAUUGCUAAGGAAAGGAGGAAGCAAGAUGUGGUUAAUCGUGUUGCAACCCAUUCCUCAAAUAUAAGAUCGACAUUUAAACCAGUAAUCGAUGGAUCCAUGCUUAAAAAUGACAUAAAACAAAGAUUAGCAAGAGAGCGCAGAGAGGAGAAAAGGAGACAGCAAGACGCCAAUAAAGAAACACAACUACUUGAAAAAGAAAGAAAGACCAAGCUCCAAUAUGAAAAACAGAUGGAGGAAAGACAGAGAAAGCUGAAGGAGCGAAAAGAGAAAGAAGAACAACGGAGAAUAGCUGCAGAAGAAAAAAGACACCAGAAGGAUGAAGCACAAAAGGAAAAAUUUACAGCCAUUCUUUAUCGUACUUUGGAACGGAGGAGACUUGCUGAUGAUUAUCAGCAAAAAAGAUGGUCAUGGGGAGGCUCUGCAAUGGCGAAUUCUGAGAGCAAAACUGCCAAUAAACGAUCUGCAUCUACUGAAAAACUUGAACAGGGUACUUCUGCUUUAAUCAGACAAAUGCCUUUGUCAUCUGCAGGCCUUCAAAAUUCCGUUGCCAAAAGGAAAACAGACAAGGAGAGAAGCUCAUCUUUAAAUAGAAGAGAUAGUAACCUACAUUCGUCUACUGAUAAAGAACAAGCCGAAAGGAAGCCACGUGUUACAGGCGUCACCAAUUAUGUAAUGCAGUAUGUCACUGUACCCUUGCGUAAAUGUACUAGCGACGAAUUGAGGGCUGUUAUGUUUCCCAUGUCGACAAUGAAAAUACCUCCUCAAACAAAAGUAGAAGAGUCUCCCUUGGAGAAAGUAGAGACACCUCCCAAGGCAAGUGUGGAUGCACCCCCCCAGGUGAAUGUGGAAGUAUUCUGCAACACAAGCAUGGAAGCGUCCCCCAAGGCAGGUGUGGGCAUGGCCCCUGAGGUGAGCACGGACUCAUUCCCUGUGGUGAGCGUGGACGUGUCGCCUGUGGUGAGCACAUAUGAUUCUGAGAUGAGCAUGGACGCAUCCCCCGAGUUGAGCAUAGAAGCACUCCCGAAGGUGGACCUGGAAACAGUUCCCAAGGUGAGCAUAGUAGCAUCCCCGGAGGCGAGCCUGGAAGCACCCCCGGAAGUGAGUCUGGAAGCACUGCCAGAGGUGAGCGUGGAAGCAGCCCCAGAGGGGAGCCUGGAAGCACCUCCCAAGGGGAGCGCAGAAGUAGCCCCCAAGGAGAGUGUGAAAGGGUCACCCAAGGAGAGCAUGGAGGCAUCUCCUGAGGCGAUGGUGAAAGCAUCCCCCAAGACAUCCCUUGAAGCAAGCAUGGAAGCAUCUCCCAAGGCAAAAGCGAGAGACGCUCCAAAGAAAUCAGAAAUGGACAAACAGGCCUUAAUCCCUAUUGCCAAGAAGCGUCUAUCAUCAUACACUGAGUGUUAUAAAUGGUCAUCAUCUCCUGAAAAUGCUUGUGGUCUGCCGUCUCCCAUCAGCACUAACAGGCAAAUCCAAAAGAACUGCCCUCCAUCACCAUUACCACUUAUUUCAAAACAGUCACCACAGACUUCUUUUCCUUAUAAAAUAAUGCCUAUUCAACACACCCUGUCUGUGCAAAGUGCAUCAAGUACUGUCAAAAAGAAAAAAGAAACAGUUUCUAAAACCACUAACAGAUGUGAGGCUUUGAGCCAAAGGCAUAUGAUCUAUGAAGAGUCUGGUAAUAAGAGUACUGCAGGUAUUAUGAAUGCCGAGGCGGCAACAAAAAUUUUGACAGAAUUGCGCCGCCUUGCUCGUGAACAAAGAGAAAAAGAGGAAGAAGAAAGACAACGGGAAGAAAUGCAGCAAAGGGUCAUUAAGAAAUCAAAAGACAUGGCAAAGGAAGCAGUUGGAGGCCAAGCAGAAGACCACUUGAAACUCAAAGAUGGGCAGCAACAAAAUGAGACUAAAAAGAAGAAAGGAUGGCUGGAUCAGGAAGACCAGGAAGCACCACUGCAGAAAGGGGACGCCAAAAUAAAAGCUCAAGAGGAAGCUGACAAACGCAAGAAAGAACACGAGAGAAUUAUGUUACAAAAUUUACAAGAACGGUUAGAAAGGAAAAAGAGAAUAGAAGAAAUUAUGAAGCGGACAAGAAAGACAGAUGUGAAUGCCUCAAAGGUCACAGAAACAUCCAGCCAUGACAUAUAUGAAGAGGCUGAGGCUGACAACGAAGAAAGCGACAAGGACUCAUUGAAUGAAAUGUUUCCAUCAGCCAUUCUAAAUGGCACAGGCUCACCUACCAAAUUUAAAAUGCCGUUCAACAAUGCCAAGAAAAUGACACACAAGCUGGUAUUUCUAGAAGAUGGUACCAGCCAGGUCCGUAAAGAGCCAAAAACAUAUUUUAAUGGCGAUUUGAAAAACUUCAGACAAAAAAGCAUGAAAGACACUUCAAUACAGGAAGUAGUUUCAAGACCAUCUUCCAAAAGAAUGACCAGUCACACAACGAAAACCAGAAAGGCGGAUGAAACCAACACCACCAGCAGAUCCUCUGCACAAACAAAAUCUGAAGGAUUCCAUGACAUCUUGCCAAAGUCCUCAGACACCUUUAGACAAUAAGAGAAGAAGCAAACCUGUUUCUCCUCAUUUGGAUAUGUAAACCUUACUCAGCCUGGGAGAUGAAUACAUCUUCCACUCUGGAUAACUCAACUCCUGGGCCCAUCAGUCCUCAAAUUUUUCUGCUUCUGACUUGAACCUGGUAAAGGAAGUGACACCGAAAAAUUGAAAGAAACUGUCAAAAGGCCACUUUGAUGUAUAUCUCAGAUGUUAAAGUCAUCUUAUUCUCUUGUGUCUAAGCAAGAGUUCUAAGUAAAGAGUGGUUUUUGUUUUCUUUGGAAAAUCAUCAUUGUCUCUCAUUCUUGUGUUGUCCCACCAAUGUGUUUGCUGGAGUGAGUGCAUCAAGGAUGCUUUCCUGAAACUGUAACUGUGGAGUUUCUAGAAGAAUCUGAUUGCAGAACUAAUUCUCUUUCAGUAUAUAUUUGAAAUCUUAAAGUAAUGCUUUUUCUUUUUCUUUUUCUUUUUUUUUUUUUUGAGACGGAGUCUUGCCCUGUCGCCCAGGCUGCAGUGCAGUGGCACAAUCUCGGCUCACUGCAACCUCCGCCUCCUCAUCUCAAGCAAUUCUCCUGUCUCAGCCUCCCCAGUAGCUGGGAUUACAGGCAUGUGCCACCACACCUGGCUAAUUUUUUUGUAUUUUAGUAGAGAUAGGGUUUUACCAUGUUCACCAGGCUAGUCUCGAAAUCCUGGCCUCAAGAGAUCCACCCGUCUUGGCCUCCCAAAGUGUUGGGAUUACAGGUGUGAGCCACUGCACCCAGCCAAGUAAUGCUUUUUCUGUGUACCAGUGACAAUUUUGACAGCUAAAAACUCACAGUUGAUCUUGUAGAGAACAGAAUAGAUUAUGCAAGGGCCGCAGGAUCGCUCACAAGAGCUGUCAGAUUGUUUCUAAUAUAAAAAUACCAAAGGUUGCAAAAUCCAGCAAAUUGUAUUUUACUGUGAUAUAUGUAUAUUUUUAACUCUACCCAUCUGUGCCAGUGAGUACACAGGCACUAAUAACCUGAAAUGCUGGGAGUCCUGUAAAGCCCCAUCUUGGAACAGUCAGCACCUUUCAUGCUCUUGUCAGUGUUUCCUUUUGAAGGACAUAUUGGUGUUUAUCUACAGAAACAUAUAUUAUUUUUAUUGUGUACAUAAAGGAGUAUAUGGCUGUUGUCCCGUGGGGUAUGUUUAAUUCCUCUAAAUGUUUAAAGUACUUUUCUGCCUGUACUCUCCAGUUCUGUCGUUGAGUAUACACUCAGGCUUGAGAUACAACCAAAAUUUGCUUGCCUUUCUCUAGCCACUGGCUGCCAGUGAGUUCGUGUGAUGGGCACACAGAAAUGCACACAGAUGUACAUACACGUAUGUAUGCACACACAGUAUAUGAUUCCAUAAAAUUCAAAUGCAGAUUAAUUCUCCUAAUGAGUUUUCAGUGUUGAAUCGUAAAUAGUCUGAAGCAGGCCAGUGUUCCUUUUGGCUGCCAGUCUUGGAUUAGUAAAAGGAGGUAAUUCUUUCAGAUUCCCUGGUUCUUUGCCACUCAGAGUAUUGUACUUUUGAUAUAGAAUAGAGAAGGUUACCUUUGGUUUAAAAACUAUUUUUAUAUACUAGCUCUUUCAUGUAUAAAACAGAGACAAUCAUCCUAACAAAAGAGUUCCUGUUAUUUUUCUGCACAAAUGUCUUGUGUUGAAACACUGUUACAGUUCCAUAUAAAUGUGUGCUAUAUAAAAUAAACUUUGGAGAUAAAA